CUUUUCCGGUCGGCGUGGUCUUGCGAGUGGAGUGUCCGCUGUGCCCGGGCCUGCACCAUGAGCGUCCCGGCCUUCAUCGACAUCAGUGAAGAAGAUCAGGCUGCUGAGCUUCGUGCUUAUCUGAAAUCUAAAGGAGCUGAGAUUUCAGAAGAGAACUCGGAAGGUGGACUUCAUGUUGAUUUAGCUCAAAUUAUUGAAGCCUGUGAUGUGUGUCUGAAGGAGGAUGAUAAAGAUGUUGAAAGUGUGAUGAACAGUGUGGUAUCCCUACUCUUGAUCCUGGAACCAGACAAGCAAGAAGCUUUGAUUGAAAGCCUAUGUGAAAAGCUGGUCAAAUUUCGCGAAGGUGAACGCCCGUCUCUGAGACUGCAGUUGUUAAGCAACCUUUUCCACGGGAUGGAUAAGAAUACUCCUGUAAGAUACACAGUGUAUUGCAGCCUUAUUAAAGUGGCAGCAUCUUGUGGGGCCAUCCAGUACAUCCCAACUGAGCUGGAUCAAGUUAGAAAAUGGAUUUCUGACUGGAAUCUCACCACUGAAAAAAAGCACACCCUUUUAAGACUACUUUAUGAGGCACUUGUGGAUUGUAAGAAGAGUGAUGCUGCUUCAAAAGUCAUGGUGGAAUUGCUCGGAAGUUACACAGAGGACAAUGCUUCCCAGGCUCGAGUUGAUGCCCACAGGUGUAUUGUACGAGCAUUGAAAGAUCCAAAUGCAUUUCUUUUUGACCACCUUCUUACUUUAAAACCAGUCAAGUUUUUGGAAGGCGAGCUUAUUCAUGAUCUUUUAACCAUUUUUGUGAGUGCUAAAUUGGCAUCAUAUGUCAAGUUUUAUCAGAAUAAUAAAGACUUCAUUGAUUCACUUGGCCUGUUACAUGAACAGAAUAUGGCAAAAAUGAGACUACUUACUUUUAUGGGAAUGGCAGUAGAAAAUAAGGAAAUUUCUUUUGACACAAUGCAGCAAGAACUUCAGAUUGGAGCUGAUGAUGUUGAAGCAUUUGUUAUUGACGCCGUAAGAACUAAAAUGGUCUACUGCAAAAUUGAUCAGACCCAGAGAAAAGUAGUUGUCAGUCAUAGCACACAUCGGACAUUUGGAAAACAGCAGUGGCAACAACUGUAUGACACACUUAAUGCCUGGAAACAAAAUCUGAACAAAGUGAAAAACAGCCUUUUGAGUCUUUCUGAUACCUGAGUUUUUAUGCUUAUAAUUUUUGUUCUUUGAAAAAAAAGCCCUAAAUCAUAGUAAAACAUUAUAAACUAAAAAAAUUUGCCUAGUCUGGACAGUUAUUGUCUCAAAUUUAUACUAAAAUCACAAACUCCAGAGGAUAUGAAGUAAUAAAUUACAAGGGGUCACAAUGUCUGUCAUACAAUACAUAAAUUCUGUUCUUUAAAAAAGGAUAUUGAAGAAGCAAUGAGCACUUUAAAGAAAGGAUAAUAUACAGAGAGAAGACAGAAGUAGAGUAAUACAAUUUCUUCACAUUAGAAAAACUUGGAAAAGCAAAGACAAACUGUAGAGCUUUAAAUACAACAGUCAUUUUAUUCUAGUAAAAACUAUACCAGAAUUUCAGUUACAUAAUUUCACUACUGAAAGCACUUAUCUACAUUAUUUUAAUCUGUUGUUUUUUUCCAACGUCUCUUCUGCUUUUCUUUUCUUUGGCUGGUUGUCAUUUUCUAAACUUAGUAAAUUUUCACUUUUAUUUAGUUGAUUCGUAAUGAGGCUCUGCCAGUCAUCAUCACCAGAAGUAUUUUUAGUCGUCUUGAUUGCCUGCAAAUGGCUUUGUAGUGGAGUUGAUAUCAGAGGCUUUGUUUUCACCUGGGAAAGAUAAACUAAUUUUACCUUCGAAAUUAUUAUACAAAAGAUUUUAAAGAGUCUGUAAAGCCUCUGCAGUUAUGAGUAUGUGGUAAAACCACCAUCUCUUGGCUGAUUUCCACUACCUUAGUAGUUCUGGCACCAGAAAAGUAUACAAUGUGAAUGUGUAGGCUUAUGUAGUAGAUCUUCAAAAUCUCUAAUAUAUAACUGAAGUAAAGUGUACAAAAACUGCCUUUUACUACUUCAUGUUUCCUCCCAUGCUUCAGAACACCAUUGUUGAAGAAACAGGAAGGGCAGUGAGAUAUUUGGAAGUUGGCAUGUUUUCAAGACACUGUAUUGGGUAAUUUUAAAAAUAGUGUGUUAAAUAACUUUUUCAUUUUAAGGUUCUUUUCUGAUGUUAAAAUACUUACUGGAAAUUUAGAAAAUAGAGUAAAGUAGAAAGAAACUAAAAAUCAUUAGUAAUCCCUUAUCCAGAGAGGCUUGUUGACAUUUUGGUAUUAUUUGCUGCUAGCGUUUUUUUCUAUUUUUAGCCUAUUUGAUCAUUCUAUAGAAUUUUAUGUAUUUUCCUCUGUGAGCAGUUUCUUAGGUCAUUAAAAACAAUUGUCUAUGGCUGCAAAAUACUCCCUUUUAUGGAUGUUUGAUAUAUCUCCUACUACUGAAUGUUUGUUUCCAGUUUAUCCCUACCAAAAAUUAAUUCGAGUUAAUUUCAUGCAAAACAAUCUUUGAUGUUUUUGAGAGAUUCCCAGAUAAAAUUUUCUCUUCAAAAGGAAUACUGGGCCAGGCACUGUGACUCAUACCUGUAAUCCCAGCACUUUGGGAAACUGAGGCGAGUGGAUUGCAUGAGCUCAGGAGUCGAAAACUAGCCUGAGCAACAUGGCAAAACCCCAUCUCUACCAAAAAUUAGCUGGGCAUGGUGGCAUGCAACUGUAGUCCCAGCUCCUCGGAGGGCUGAGGUGCAAGGAUCAUUUGAGCCCAGGAGGUGAAGGUUGCAAUGAGCCAAGAUCAUGCCAUUGCACUCCAGCCUGGACAACAGAGUGAGACCCUCUCUCAAAAAUAAAUAAUAGAUAAAACAAAAGGAAUACUGAAUUGUUUUCAAAAUAACAAUUAUGGUGGGCUUUCUUUUAAGAUAGGGUCUCACCCUGUCACCUAGGCUGGAGUGCAGUGGCACAAUCACAGCUCAUUGCAGCCUUGACCUCCCUGGAUUCAGGUGAUCCUCCCACCUUCACCUCCUGAGUACCUUGGACUACAGGCAUGUGCCACCACACCCAGGUAAUUUUUGUAUUUUUUGCCAUGUUGCCCAGGCUGGUCUCUCUUAACUCUUGGGCUCAAGUGAUCUGACCAUCUCGGUCUCCCAAAGUUCUAGGAUUACAGGAGUGAGCCAUACUGUGUUGUGUUUUAGUUGAAAGGGAUAUACACGUGUAUUUUAGAAAUAUGAAACAGGAUAAGAAUUACAUUAAAAUCACCCAAGAUCCCAACCACCAUUAAAGAGUUUGUGUAAAUCUUCUGGUCUCUUUUCUGUAUACACUUUUUAAAUACUGGGGUCAUAUUUUUAUUGGUUUAUAUGCUAUGUUAAACAUUUUUAGCAUUUCCUCCUGUUCUUAAGUCUGUUAAGAGGAUAGCUCCAUCAUAUUCUGUGUUCUGCAAAUUAUUUCUGGACAUUUAAAUUGUAAGAAAAUGGUCACUGUUAACUAGGCUGCAGUGAUUAUCAUUUGUUCAUAAAUCUUUGUGAAGAUCUUUGGGUACUGCCUUACAUUAAAAUCUUUUUCAAUUUGACCAGUAAAAGUGGCAUGUUAGUAACAUUGUCAUUUUCAGUGUUAGAUUAUGUAGUACUAAGUUUAUUUUAUUUUAUUUUUGAGACAGAGUCUUGCACUGUCGCCCAGGCUGGAGUGCAGUGGCGCCAUCUCAGCUCACUGCAACCUCCACCUCCCAGGUUCAAGCGAUUCUUCUGCCUCAGCCUCCCGAGUAGCUGGGAUUACAGGCACCCACCACGAUGCCCAGCUAAUUUUUUGUAUUUUUAGUAGAGACAGGGUUUCACUAUGUUGUCCAGGCUGGUCUCGAACGCCUGACCUCAUGAUCCACCUGCCUCGGCCUCCCAAAGUGUUGGGAUUACAGGCAUGAGCCACCCUGCCCGACCUAGUAAUACUUUUUUUUUUUUUUUUUUUUAAUGAACUUAAAUGUUUAGAAUGGUAAGUUCACGGCUCCCUAAGGAGUGUUCCUUUUGGAUUGCUCUGUUUGGCUCCCUCCCUGAAAUCCUAUAGUCAGCCACUGGUCCCCUCAGAGAGUUUUACCUCUGAUCUUUGGGGUGAUUCUUUGUUCAUAUUUAUCUGAUUGGCUUUGUUCUUCCAAAAGUGUCUGCACAGGACUGCUAAGAGAACCUAGGCAAGUCAUUUAAUUUUUCUGGGCUUCAGUUUACUCAUUAGCUUCUUUUAGUUCCCAGAUGCUAUUACUGGAAAGAAUAACUAGUAAUGGAUAAAAACCUACAUAAAUAUUUCCUAUUUUGCCAUCAAAGUGCUGGGUUCAUUUUGGUGUAUUUGGCAUCCAAGUACAAAUUAACAGUUUCCCAAAAUCCUGAUUCUUUGACUUUUUUAUCUUGAUGAUGGAAAGGAAGGACACGUUUACUUGCUUUAGUUUCUUUCCCCUUAACUACCCACUUGCUGAGAGGGGUAGGAGCAGGGAUUGGCUUUAGAGAAACAAGAUACAGUGUAGAUUAGCUAAUGUUUGCGCUUAACAAAACUUGUCCUGUUUAACUUACCUGAGGGUUCUGCAGCCUACCGCAGUAAUUUUAGUUCUAGCUGUUUUCAGAUAUAUUGCCUUGUAUCUUCGUUCUUUCGUCUCCUAUCCUUUUUAGAAAUUUAUCACCUGUUUCUCUUUCAGCCUGACUUACAAAAUCUAAUUUUUGGCCUAAAAAUUUCCCCUAGCUUGGUACUAGUCCUUUUAUUUCUGCCUGUGAUUAUAUUUUAAAAUUAAACUUAAAUGAAUCUAAUUCAUUGGAUAUAUAAAAAAAAAAGUAAGUGGCUUGCUUUGCUUACUCUGGUUUUCCAUCCUCAUUCCUGGAUAUAAUCAAGAUUGCAGUAGGCUAACAAUCUAAUGCUGAAAACAAGAAUGAAAAACAUACCAUCUUUUCAAGUUACUUUGGACCCAUAGAGAGAAAGUGGAUUGGUACUUAAUACCUUCCCUGAAUUUAACAGAAUUGAUGUGGACUGUACAUAAAAUAUGUUGAAAAAUAAAACUAUUUUUUUGGCUAUAA